GAGAAGUGAUCCAGACCUCUUAGAAGUUGGGUUGGGGCUGCCUUAUGGGUGGACAGGGAUCUCUAGGGAACCUCACACCCAUUUCCCCCAGAAGCAAAAGAGUAAAUUCUAUUAUUGCCAACCAACCAGGACUUUUCCAUGCCAGACAUCCUGCCAUGAGGAAAUUUCAGAGCGAGGACGCCCAGCAUGCCGCCCUUCUGUAGGAAUGCAAAGUUAGGCCUCCUUUCUUUCCUGAUUUGUGCUGGAAGGAGCUUAUUACCUUUGGGGAAGAAUGCCUUUUGGUUAGAAAGAAUUGAAAAUAAUAAUACCCUCUGGGAAAAGGCUCAAAGUCAGAAAAUGAGAUACAAGACAUCCUUGGUGAUGAGGAAACGAUUACGGCUUUACCGAAACACUCUUAAAGAGUCAAGUAGCAGCUCUGGACACCAUGGCCCCCAGCUCACCGCCGCCUCCAGCCCCUCGGUGUUCCCGGGCCUCCACGAGGAGCCUCCCCAGGCCUCCCCCAGCCGUCCUUUGAAUGGACUCCUGCGUCUGGGGCUCCCUGGAGACAUGUACGCGCGGCCGGAGCCCUUCCCGCCAGGGCCUGCGGCCCGCAGCGACGCCCUGGCAGCUGCCGCAGCCCUGCAUGGCUACGGGGGCAUGAACCUGACGGUGAACCUCGCUGCGCCCCACGGUCCUGGCGCUUUCUUCCGCUACAUGCGCCAGCCCAUCAAACAGGAGCUCAUCUGCAAGUGGCUGGCGGCCGACGGCACCGCGACCCCGAGCCUCUGCUCCAAAACUUUCAGCACCAUGCACGAGCUGGUCACGCACGUCACCGUGGAGCACGUCGGCGGCCCGGAACAGGCCAACCACAUUUGCUUCUGGGAGGAGUGUCCGCGCCAGGGAAAGCCCUUCAAAGCCAAAUACAAACUUGUAAAUCACAUCCGCGUGCACACGGGCGAGAAGCCCUUCCCUUGUCCUUUCCCGGGGUGUGGGAAGGUCUUUGCUAGAUCAGAAAAUCUCAAAAUACACAAACGAACUCACACAGGCGAGAAGCCCUUCAGAUGCGAGUUCGAGGGCUGCGAGCGGCGCUUCGCCAACAGCAGCGACCGUAAGAAGCAUUCGCACGUGCACACUAGCGACAAGCCAUACACGUGCAAGGUGCGGGGCUGCGACAAGUGCUACACGCACCCCAGCUCGCUGCGUAAGCACAUGAAGGUGCACGGGCGCUCGCCGCCGCCCAGCUCUGGCUACGAUUCGGCUACACCGUCUGCCCUCGUGUCGCCCUCGUCGGACUGCGGCCACAAGUCCCAGGUGGCCUCCUCGGCGGCGGUGGCGGCGCGUACCGCCGACUUGAGCGAAUGAUGUCCACCGCGUUGCUCGCAAGGUAAUCUCGCUCCGCGCAGCUGAGCGCCCCGCAUCUCGCGCCUGCUACAUCAAAGGGCCCGCGCACAAAGCAGUGUUUCUUCGCCACGGUGCAUCUUCAUGGUAAGUUAGGAUUUCUAUGGCAAUGUGCAAGUCGCACUGAAAUCCUGAAAGGCCAAGCCUGGAGCCCGUCCAGGCUUUUCAUUAAGGACAUAAUAUUUACGUCUAACAGACCUUUUUUCUUGUGUAUACAAGUAUAUAUUUUUGUUUGACGCGGACUAAAUCAUUUUCAUUUAAUUUCCGGUAAACAAAACCCACGCGAAUGGGCACUUGUACCCGAUCAUAAUAAAAAUGGAUAAUAAUGUGAAGGAAGAAAAGAGCCGCUUGAAUCGCCGCUCAGCCCCCUUUGUUUCUGCUUUCUGCGGUGAUCAGAGGGCGCGUUUGGGUUUGAUGGCGAGUUUCUAAAGGCGAGGAAAUGGUUUGUAAGAGGGGAAAGAAAAGGAGAAAGGUCUAAUCAAGCUCGGGUUGUUCAAAGAGUCGGGUUUUGGGGUUGAAAGUGUGAGUUUGACGGUGCAUCAGCAUGCCGCGUUAGGCUCGCCAUGGAAAUACGCGCGGGGAGCGGCCGCUUCAAAGGCGGCACACUUCACUACAGACACUCUAUUAAGAUACAUUUGCGCUGACCUUUGCUUUCACGCCAUUUAAUACUGUCACUGCGCUCUCCAGUAUAUACUUCCUUUCUAGAACCCGACUUGCCCACGUUUAGGGGUUCACUCUGCACCCUGAUGUGGGAGGCUUUGGCGCAGGGGACACUUUCAGGAAAGGGAGGAGCACAAGGACUCUGUGCAUCUUGACUGCACCCCAAAGAGGCUCCAGGAUCAGGAGUGAAAGAUUUUAAAGCAGCCUCCGAAGCUUAACAAAUGAGCAUUCCAAGCUCAGUUUUGUGCAAAUCGCCUUUCUGACUCUUGAGUAGGAUGGAGGCUUAAAUUUAAUGGCGACUUGGGGGGAAGGGAGCCACCCUGGGGGAGUCUGAGGAGUUCAGACUGUGCCCUUGGGAAUUUCCACUCUGGCUUUCCGUGCCACUCUUCUUCCUUUCCAUCCCAAAAGUCUCUUGCGGCCCCUGAAACUUGUUUCUUUCUAAGGCAGGGUGUGUGGUACCCUUAGGCCUGGACUAGUCCUAGAUGCAAACUCAAGAGCCCAAGGCCAAGGGGAUGUGGGGAAGAUGGCAGGAAAGUUAGAAGUCCAUGUUCCCUUAAUUGUCUUGUUGUUUAUUUUAUCCAAGUACCCCAGUGAAUAGGGGAAAAAUAAACACAGUGAAAAAAAAAAUCAAACAGUGGAGUCUUCUUUAGUGCCAGUCCUUGUGGUUGAAUAAAAAGGAUGGUCCGCUUUCUAUUGAGCUGAGAAAUCUUUGAAGUGGGAGUUAUUAUCUGAGACAUUCCUGCUUGUCGUCCUAACAACGCUGAUGAAACGUAAAAGGUUCUUUGUCAGCGAUUUGUUCUCCUCUCUGUCAAACUCCCUCUGCCCCGUUAGUUUCAAACCGUUUCUAAAGAGAUAAAAAUCAAACUUCUUUUAAAACAAUAUCCACACACUGCAUCAAUACAUAACUUUAGGUCUAAGUCUUGCUAAGGGAUAAACAAAAGCAAUGCCUAGACAUCAGGGUCAGGGCCUGGUCUGGUGAAGUAUGCAGAAGUUGGGGGGCCCUCGGGACAAGCUUUGGGACAUGAGGAAAAGAAUGCAGAGAGGGUGCAAGCAGAAUACAUACCCUAAGUCCAUAAUUGUGUUUCUGCUUCUUUCUGCUCUGGUUUGCAUUCAAUCAGCCCAAGUUGGGUCACAUAGAUGGGUUUCCUUUGGGUACCCCUCAGGCUCCUAAUAUUCUUGCCCAGGAUCCUUGGAACUUAAGAAUGCAGCCAAGCAAUUGUUAAUAUCUCCUGCUCCUUCAAAGCCACCUCUGCUAAAAAUAGACCCAUUGUGUGUUUCUUCUCACUAGCAGCAAUCAACAAGCCCUUUCUGCCGUUAAUAAGAAGGAGAAUAGCUGAAGGAGAGAGAUAUUUUAUUAAUUUCCUGUUUCCUUCAGAAUCUUGGCAAUUGAAGUUUAGAAGGUUUGGUCUACAACACAGUGAUCGAAAAUGCAUGUAAAUGCCCAUCCUUCCCUUCAUUCACGUGUGAAGUUGUUCAUUUUAUAUUGUGCCCAGCAAAGAAACUUUCACCCAGUUCAGGUUUCCCCAAAACUCCUGUGGUGGUUUUAAAGGUGGUUUAAAUAAAUAAGGAUGUGCUGGUCCCCCUACUCUGUGUGUGCUGAAUAAAUGGCUUGUAAAGAAGUUUUUCCAAGCUGUAACCCAUGCUGUUAUUAUAGUUGCUGCAAAAUGUUCUUCCUGAUAUUGAUUUUAUUUGUUAACUGAAGGUCUCCAUAUGUUUGUUUAUAUUGCUAAUUUAUGAGAAAAUGUAAUAAUUGCAAUGAAUGUGAAUUAUACAGACAGGCAAACAUUUUGUAAUCAUAAUUCACAUAUACACAAAAGCCUGGCUGAAAUCUUUAGACUAUUUGUACCCUCUCUACCCACACUGUUUGUGAUUUAUCAUCUGUCUCUUUAGUGUCAGUUAAAUUAUGAACUAACUUGAAAAUAAAAGUUGUUUGACUGAAAGUGAUUGUUGAAUGAACAACAAAGUUGAAAGCCAUGGCUUGAUCUUGUAAAUAUAUAAAUGUAAAUGAUAUUAAAUCUGUGAUUCCUUUUCCCUCCAAAGGCUUUUGUGUACAUGGCGCUGCAUUUGGCUAUUUUCUUUGGAAAUAAAUAAUGUGAUGUUUCUCUUCCUCUUUUG